ACGUGUCCGCCGGAGUUUCUCCACCAGCAACAUGGCCGCCGCCUGAGAGGAGAGCCGGGCCGCCGCCGUCUCUGCAGCCCGCGGGUAACUGGGCCGUUGCCGCCGUCCGCGCUCGGCCCCCGCGGAGAGAUCGAGCUGAAGGACUGCGCGGCUGGCUCUCCUCUAGUAUGGCCAAUGAAGAGGAUGACCCAGUUGUACAGGAGAUCGAUGUGUACUUGGCCAAGAGUCUGGCGGAAAAGCUGUAUCUAUUUCAGUACCCUGUGCGUCCAGCCUCGAUGACCUACGAUGACAUUCCGCACCUCUCAGCCAAGAUCAAGCCCAAGCAGCAGAAGGUAGAGCUUGAGAUGGCCAUCGACACCCUGAACCCCAACUAUUGCCGCAGCAAAGGGGAGCAGAUUGCGCUGAACGUGGACGGGGCCUGCGCCGACGAGACCAGCACGUAUUCCUCGAAGCUGAUGGACAAGCAGACCUUCUGCUCUUCCCAGACCACCAGUAACACAUCCCGUUAUGCCGCUGCACUCUACAGGCAAGGUGAGCUCCACCUGACACCUUUACAUGGCAUCCUGCAGCUGCGGCCCAGCUUCUCCUACCUGGAUAAGGCUGACGCCAAGCACCGGGAGAGGGAGGCGGCCAACGAGGCAGGGGACUCUUCACAGGAUGAGGCGGAAGACGAUGUUAAGCAGAUCACGGUGCGGUUCUCCCGGCCGGAGUCAGAGCAGGCCCGCCAGCGCCGUGUGCAGUCCUAUGAGUUCCUGCAGAAGAAGCACGCAGAGGAGCCCUGGGUCCACCUGCAUUACUAUGGCCUGAGGGACAGUCGCUCUGAGCAUGAGCGUCAGUACCUGCUGUGCCCCGGCUCAAGCGGGGUGGAGAACACGGAGCUCGUCAAGUCACCCAGUGAGUACCUGAUGAUGCUGAUGCCACCCAGCCAGGAGGAGGAGAAAGACAAGCCUGUGGCCCCCAGCAACGUCCUGUCGAUGGCCCAGCUGCGCACGCUGCCCCUGGCCGAUCAGAUCAAGAUCCUGAUGAAGAAUGUGAAGGUCAUGCCUUUUGCCAACUUGAUGAGCCUCCUGGGCCCCUCCAUCGAUUCCGUGGCUGUUCUGCGGGGCAUCCAGAAGGUGGCGAUGUUGGUCCAAGGGAACUGGGUGGUGAAGAGUGACAUCCUAUACCCCAAGGACUCGUCCAGCCCUCACAGCGGCGUGCCUGCUGAGGUGCUCUGCAGGGGCCGAGACUUCGUUAUGUGGAAGUUCACGCAGAGCCGCUGGGUGGUUAGGAAAGAGGUGGCAACCGUGACCAAACUCUGCGCCGAGGAUGUGAAGGACUUCCUGGAGCACAUGGCCGUGGUGAGGAUCAACAAAGGCUGGGAGUUCAUUCUGCCUUAUGAUGGGGAGUUCAUCAAGAAGCACCCGGAUGUGGUCCAGCGGCAGCACAUGCUGUGGACGGGUAUCCAGGCCAAACUGGAAAAAGUCUAUAAUCUUGUAAAGGAAACCAUGCCAAAGAAGCCGGAUGCACAAUCAGGGCCUGCCGGGCUGGUCUGUGGGGACCAGCGGAUCCAAGUAGCCAAAACCAAGGCCCAGCAGAACCACGCGUUGCUGGAGCGGGAGCUGCAGCGGCGGAAGGAGCAGCUGCGGGUGCCUGCGGUCCCGCCCGGUGUGCGGAUCAAGGAGGAGCCCGUGAGCGAGGAGGGCGAGGAGGACGAGGAGCAGGAGGCGGAGGAGGAGCCCAUGGACACUUCCCCCAGCGGCCUCCACAGCAAGCUGGCCAACGGGCUGCCUCUCGGGCGGGCUGCGGGCACAGACAGCUUCAACGGGCACCCGCCCCAGGGCUGCGCCAGCACCCCUGUGGCUCGGGAACUGAAGGCCUUCGUGGAGGCCACCUUUCAGAGACAGUUUGUGCUCACGCUGAGCGAACUCAAGCGCCUCUUCAAUCUGCACUUGGCCAGCCUGCCCCCCGGCCACACACUCUUCAGCGGCAUCUCGGACCGCAUGCUACAGGACACGGUGCUGGCCGCCGGUUGCAAGCAGAUACUGGUGCCUAUGAAGAAACUGAGGCUCCAAGGAAUGAAAUGUACGUUUAAAGGUCACUACCUAGGAGGUAGUAGAGCUGGAAUUUGGACCUCAGUAUAGUGGCCUGGAGUUUUGAAUCCUUUCUGCUCAGCUAAGAUGAGCUGCUUCCCCACAGCUGCGCCACGCCCCAGCUUGGGCCUGGGUCCUGGCGGCCUCCCUGUGCAUCAGAAGCAAGCUGACCAGCUCAGCGCUGUGCUCUCAGCACUUCCAGUGCCAGGCCUUGAGUGUGGUAUUGCAAGCCUCCUGCCCCUUCCCCCUGGGCUGCUUUUCUGUCACUGGGAGGGGCCCUGACGGGGGAGCAGAGUGCUUGCUGGGGACCGUUUCCCUGCGCUGAGGAUAGAGAGCGCCAGGUGCUGCCUGAGGCACGCCUUUCCCGUGCUCCUUUUCCACAAGGCUCUGCCCAGACCUGGCAGCAAAAUGGGGUGAGGUGGGGCUGUGGUGGUCUCUAAGAAAGCAUUGAUGUUUUCAUUGCCAAGGUCAGGAGCGGGCCUGCAGCCUUGGGUGAUGAUCUGAGGCCAAGGCCCAUCCCUGUGUAUGAGGAAUAGAAACUAGGACAGGAGGCCUUGUGGAGCCUAGGCUGUCUCAGGGGAUCGGCCCUGCUGGCAGGCAGCCCCCUGUGGGAGGUACUGGCAGAGUUCGGAGCUCCUGCCCACCCAGCACAUGGGUCUGGGUCUCCACAAGCUCACCUUUCUUCAUGAGCUGGGCCAGGACAGGCAGGACACCUGCCUGACAUUAGUUGUUUUGGGCCGCUGGAGUGGACAGAGGUGAGGGGUGGGACAUGGCCACCCUCAGACACCCUCACCCCUCCUUCCGGACCCCCUCUGUCCAUGUUGCUUUGGGGUGGGGCCAGCGUCUCCAGGAGACACCAUGGCCCUAACUGUAAUGCUCUCCUUGCCAUCCUGACAAGGAGACUGUAUUGUAGUCACAUCCAAGACGUAAGAGACCUCCGAUCCCAGCCACCUCUGUGUUGUACAUGAGGGAGCUGAGGUCCAGGGCAAGUGAAUAGAUCGAGAACUUGACUUGAACUCCUGGUUCUGCUGCUUAUUAGCUGUGUGACCAUGGACAGUGAGCAAACCUCUCUGAGCUUACUUUUCCCCAUGUACUACCUCCCCAGUUUCUAAUGCUCAAAUGCAAAUGUGUAUUGGAGGCCUCACAGGGCUUUUACUGGUAGUAACCAUUAUUGCUACUUGUGUGAUGGAACCAGGACUGGAAACUACCAUCCCAGAUGCCCCCUCCCCUGUCCCCUUCUCUCCAGGACCCAGGCCUGUGUCACACUUGUCCUGGUCUACCUUUGGACCAAGUGGCCUGGAUUGCUUGGGAGUCAGGCAGUGCCUCUAACCCACACUGACAUGGUACAUGUGGGAAGCAGUUGAAAAGAACCCCCAGGGUACCCCAAGAGUUAUGGGGAAGGGGGCGCCCCUCCAUCAGGGUUGGCAUCUUCAGGAGGGAGGACUCUGGGUGUUAAAGCACAGUUGAGUUGGUGCCAGGCUGAUGGGAAACAGACGCAGCUUCCCCACUGUACGGAGGAUAUCUGCAGACUCGAAGCCGGGCAUUUCACUGGGCCCAUCACACUCCCCCUCUCGCUGAAGCCCUGUCAGGCCCUGGGGGGUGUGCUGGCCUCCUCCCCAUGGUGAGGUGAGAGGCACAGGUUUGUGGCUGCCCAAGGCCCUCAGAGAUGGUGAGUAGCAGAAGCUGGGAUUGGAACCCAUGUUCCUGCAUCUGGGCUGGGGCAGACAGGGAGGGAUGAGGCAAGCAAAUGGAUCCAUGGGGUAGAGAUGGACAAGCAACUCACCCCUGGGCCUUGGUCAGUUUCCCCCCCAGACUGCUGCUUCCCCGGAUGAGCAGAAGGUGUUUGCCCUCUGGGAGUCUGGAGACAUGAGUGAUCAG